AGAGUUUCUCAAGAAGCCGAGAGAGGGACAGAGGCUGAGCCUGGGGGGAGGGCUGCAGGGGACUGAGAGGGGAGUGUAGGCAGUGGGGGUGAGGGGGACAGGGAGGAGGUGGAGAAGACGGCAAGGGGCAGCAGGGUGACUGGGGCAGAGGGAGCCCCCACCCCACGCCCAGGGCAGGCCAGGAGUCAUAAGGAGAGGGGACAACAGGAAGGGGCGACAAACGGGGAGGGGAAAGGGAGGCGGAGGGGCAGCGAAGUGAAGCAGGGAGGGUCGCAGUGUGAACAAGAGUGCGAGGAAGGGUCAAGGUGGAGGGAGGAGAGGGGAGAGUUAGGGAGAAACAGCUGCAGGAGAGGCGCGGGGAGGAAGCCUUAGGGGUGGGGGAAGGGAGAGGGGAGUUGAGAAUUAGGGAGGAGGUGGUAGAGUCCGGGUAGUGAGCGGAGGGACAGGAAGGGUAGGGCAAGAAAGGGAGAGGGGACAGGAGGGAAGGGUGGGCCAAAGCGGUGAGAAAGGAGGGCCAGCCAGUUGGGUGGGGGAGAGGGCCGAGGCCCGGGGGCAGGAGUGCAGGGCUCUGAGGCGGGGAGAGGAGAGGAGAGAAGAGCCGCGGGGGGCCCAGCCCGGAGCCAGGAUGCCCGCGCCGCGCGCCCGGGAGCAGCCCCGCGUGCCCGGGGAGCGCCAGCCGCUGCUGCCUCGCGGUGCGCGGGGCCCUCGACGGUGGCGGCGGGCGGCGGGCGCGGCCGUGCUGCUGGUGGAGAUGCUGGAGCGCGCCGCCUUCUUCGGCGUCACCGCCAACCUCGUGCUGUACCUCAACAGCACCAACUUCAACUGGACCGGCGAGCAGGCGACGCGCGCCGCGCUGGUAUUCCUGGGCGCCUCCUACCUGCUGGCGCCCGUGGGCGGCUGGCUGGCCGACGUGUACCUGGGCCGCUACCGCGCGGUCGCGCUCAGCCUGCUGCUCUACCUGGCCGCCUCGGGCCUGCUGCCCGCCACCGCCUUCCCCGACGGCCGCAGCUCCUUCUGCGGAGAGAUGCCCGCGUCGCCGCUGGGACCUGCCUGCCCCUCGGCCGGCUGCCCGCGCUCCUCGCCCAGCCCCUACUGCGCGCCCGUCCUCUACGCGGGCCUGCUGCUACUCGGCCUGGCCGCCAGCUCCGUCCGGAGCAACCUCACCUCCUUCGGUGCCGACCAGGUGAUGGAUCUCGGCCGCGACGCCACCCGCCGCUUCUUCAACUGGUUUUACUGGAGCAUCAACCUGGGUGCUGUGCUGUCGCUGCUGGUGGUGGCGUUUAUUCAGCAGAACAUCAGCUUCCUGCUGGGCUACAGCAUCCCUGUGGGCUGUGUGGGCCUGGCAUUUUUCAUCUUCCUCUUUGCCACCCCCGUCUUCAUCACCAAGCCCCCGAUGGGCAGCCAAGUGUCCUCUAUGCUUAAGCUCGCUCUCCAAAACUGCUGCCCCCAGCUGUGGCAACGACACUCGGCCAGAGACCGUCAAUGUGCCCGCGUGCUGGCCGACGAGAGGUCUCCCCAGCCAGGGGCUUCCCCGCAAGAGGACAUCGCCAACUUCCAGGUGCUGGUGAAGAUCUUGCCCGUCAUGGUGACCCUGGUGCCCUACUGGAUGGUCUACUUCCAGAUGCAGUCCACCUAUGUCCUGCAGGGUCUUCACCUCCACAUCCCAAACAUUUUCCCAGCCAACCCGGCCAACAUCUCUGUGGCCCUGAGAGCCCAGGGCAGCAGCUACACGAUCCCGGAAGCCUGGCUCCUCCUGGCCAAUGUUGUGGUGGUGCUGAUUCUGGUCCCUCUGAAGGACCGCUUGAUCGACCCUUUACUGCUGCGGUGCAAGCUGCUUCCCUCUGCUCUGCAGAAGAUGGCGCUGGGGAUGUUCUUUGGUUUUACCUCCGUCAUUGUGGCAGGAGUCCUGGAGAUGGAGCGCUUACACUACAUCCACCACAACGAGACCGUGUCCCAGCAGAUUGGGGAGGUCCUGUACAACGCGGCACCACUGUCCAUCUGGUGGCAGAUCCCUCAGUACCUGCUCAUUGGGAUCAGUGAGAUCUUUGCCAGCAUCCCAGGCCUGGAGUUUGCCUACUCAGAGGCCCCGCGCUCCAUGCAGGGCGCCAUCAUGGGCAUCUUCUUCUGCCUGUCGGGGGUGGGCUCACUGUUGGGCUCCAGCCUAGUGGCACUGCUGUCCUUGCCCGGGGGCUGGCUGCACUGCCCCAAGGACUUUGCUGAAGAGGAAUUGUAGACACCCCUGGAGAUCUUCAGGAAGUCAAACAUUAGGAACAUCAACAAUUGCCGGAUGGACCUCUACUUCUUCCUGCUGGCUGGCAUUCAGGCCGUCACGGCUCUCCUAUUUGUCUGGAUCGCUGGACGCUAUGAGAGGGCGUCCCAGGGCCCAGCCUCCCACAGCCGUUUCAGCAGGGACAGGGGCUGAACAGGCCCUAUUCCAGCCCCCUUGCUUCACUCUACCGGACAGACGGCAGCAGUCCCAGCUCUGGUUUCCUUCUCGGUUUAUUCUGUUAGAAUGAAAUGGUUCCCAUAAAUAAGGGGCAUGAGCCCUUCCUCACGA